AGACGUUUCCUUGGCUCUUCUGGCGCCAAAAUGUCGUUCGUGGCAGGGGUUAUUCGGCGGCUGGACGAGACAGUGGUGAACCGCAUCGCGGCGGGGGAAGUUAUCCAGCGGCCAGCUAAUGCUAUCAAAGAGAUGAUUGAGAACUGGUACGGAGGGAGUCGAGCCGGGCUCACUUAAGGGCUACGACUUAACGGGCCGCGUCACUCAAUGGCGCGGACACGCCUCUUUGCCCGGGCAGAGGCAUGUACAGCGCAUGCCCACAACGGCGGAGGCCGCCGGGUUCCCUGACGUGCCAGUCAGGCCUUCUCCUUUUCCGCAGACCGUGUGUUUCUUUACCGCUCUCCCCCGAGACCUUUUAAGGGUUGUUUGGAGUUUUAGAUGCAAAAUCCACAAGUAUUCAAGUGAUUGUUAAAGAGGGAGGCCUGAAGUUGAUUCAGAUCCAAGACAAUGGCACCGGGAUCAGGAACAAUAUACGCAAAGACUAUUAAAUGGAAGCAUACCUGACAUGUUAAAGGACUAUCAAGGAGGCCAGUUUGUCUAGAGGCUGAAAAGGAAAGAGUAAUAGGAGAUGAGGUCUGAGUGAAAACACGUAAAUCCUUGUGGGCCAAGAAAGAAGAUCUGGAUAUUGUAUGUGAAAGGUUCACUACUAGUAAACUGCAGUCCUUUGAGGAUUUAGCCAGUAUUUCUACCUAUGGCUUUCGAGGUGAGGCUUUGGCCAGCAUAAGCCAUGUGGCUCAUGUUACUAUUACAACGAAAACAGCUGAUGGAAAGUGUGCAUACAGAGCAAGUUACUCAGAUGGAAAACUGAAAGCCCCUCCUAAACCAUGUGCUGGCAAUCAAGGGACCCAGAUCACGGUGGAGGACCUUUUUUACAACAUAGCCACGAGGAGAAAAGCUUUAAAAAAUCCAAGUGAAGAAUAUGGGAAAAUUUUGGAAGUUGUUGGCAGGUAUUCAGUACACAAUGCAGGCAUUAGUUUCUCAGUUAAAAAACAAGGAGAGACAGUAGCUGAUGUUAGGACACUACCCAAUGCCUCAACCGUGGACAAUAUUCGCUCCAUCUUUGGAAAUGCUGUUAGUCGAGAACUGAUAGAAAUUGGAUGUGAGGAUAAAACCCUAGCCUUCAAAAUGAAUGGUUACAUAUCCAAUGCAAACUACUCAGUGAAGAAGUGCAUCUUCUUACUCUUCAUCAACCAUCGUCUGGUAGAAUCAACUUCCUUGAGAAAAGCCAUAGAAACAGUGUAUGCAGCCUAUUUGCCCAAAAACACACACCCAUUCCUGUACCUCAGUUUAGAAAUCAGUCCCCAGAAUGUGGAUGUUAAUGUGCACCCCACAAAGCAUGAAGUUCACUUCCUGCACGAGGAGAGCAUCCUGGAGCGGGUGCAGCAGCACAUCGAGAGCAAGCUCCUGGGCUCCAAUUCCUCCAGGAUGUACUUCACCCAGACUUUGCUACCAGGACUUGCUGGCCCCUCUGGGGAGAUGGUUAAAUCCACAACAAGUCUGACCUCGUCUUCUACUUCUGGAAGUAGUGAUAAGGUCUAUGCCCACCAGAUGGUUCGUACAGAUUCCCGGGAACAGAAGCUUGAUGCAUUUCUGCAGCCUCUGAGCAAACCCCUGUCCAGUCAGCCCCAGGCCAUUGUCACAGAGGAUAAGACAGAUAUUUCUAGUGGCAGGGCUAGGCAGCAAGAUGAGGAGAUGCUUGAACUCCCAGCCCCUGCUGAAGUGGCUGCCAAAAAUCAGAGCUUGGAGGGGGAUACAACAAAGGGGACUUCAGAAAUGUCAGAGAAGAGAGGACCUACUUCCAGCAACCCCAGAAAGAGACAUCGGGAAGAUUCUGAUGUGGAAAUGGUGGAAGAUGAUUCCCGAAAGGAAAUGACUGCAGCUUGUACCCCCCGGAGAAGGAUCAUUAACCUCACUAGUGUUUUGAGUCUCCAGGAAGAAAUUAAUGAGCAGGGACAUGAGGUUCUCCGGGAGAUGUUGCAUAACCACUCCUUCGUGGGCUGUGUGAAUCCUCAGUGGGCCUUGGCACAGCAUCAAACCAAGUUAUACCUUCUCAACACCACCAAGCUUAGUGAAGAACUGUUCUACCAGAUACUCAUUUAUGAUUUUGCCAAUUUUGGUGUUCUCAGGUUAUCGGAGCCAGCACCGCUCUUUGACCUUGCCAUGCUUGCCUUAGAUAGUCCAGAGAGUGGCUGGACAGAGGAAGAUGGUCCCAAAGAAGGACUUGCUGAAUACAUUGUUGAGUUUCUGAAGAAGAAGGCUGAGAUGCUUGCAGACUAUUUCUCUUUGGAAAUUGAUGAGGAAGGGAACCUGAUUGGAUUACCCCUUCUGAUUGACAACUAUGUGCCCCCUUUGGAGGGACUGCCUAUCUUCAUUCUUCGACUAGCCACUGAGGUGAAUUGGGACGAAGAAAAGGAAUGUUUUGAAAGCCUCAGUAAAGAAUGCGCUAUGUUCUAUUCCAUCCGGAAGCAGUACAUAUCUGAGGAGUCGACCCUCUCAGGCCAGCAGAGUGAAGUGCCUGGCUCCAUUCCAAACUCCUGGAAGUGGACUGUGGAACACAUUGUCUAUAAAGCCUUGCGCUCACACAUUCUGCCUCCUAAACAUUUCACAGAAGAUGGAAAUAUCCUGCAGCUUGCUAACCUGCCUGAUCUAUACAAAGUCUUUGAGAGGUGUUAAAUAUGGUUAUUUAUGCACUGUGGGAUGUGUUCUUCUUUCUCUGUAUUCCGAUACAAAGUGUUGUAUCAAAGUGUGAUAUACAAAGUGUACCAACAUAAGUGUUGGUAGCACUUAAGACUUAUACUUGCCUUCUGAUAGUAUUCCUUUAUACACAGUGGAUUGAUUAUAAAUAAAUAGAUGUGUCUUAACAUAA